GGGGCUAGCCGGAUCCGCUGACUGAUGGUGGGGCGCAAGCAGGGUUGGAGCUGCAGGGUUACGGGAAUAAAACCGGGAAAGCCGGUUAGUACGCAAAGGAAAUGCAUCCUGGGGGUUUGGGGCUUUCUAGAGGCCGGGGCUCUUGGUUGUAGGAUAGAUACUGGGGGAUGGUUCUUGAAACAUCAGAGGUGAGGCCUGGAGCCCCAAAUCUGAGGUUCCUAACUACCGAAUUAGUAUAUGCCAGAGGUGGUAAACAGUGUGAGGGGCGGGGUUAUCACAGAGGGUGUCGCGGGGCAGGUGGUGCACGGGAUUAGACACCAAGUUGGACUUGGAAGCCUGGCUUAGAAAGAAAAGGUUUUUGGGCCGGGGGCGGUGGUUCACACCUGUAAUCCUAGCACUUUGCAAGGCCAAGGCGGGAGGAUCGCUUGAGCCCAGGAGUUUGAGGCCAGCUUGGGCAACAUAGGCUCCAUCUCUUUAAAAACAAAAGCGAAACAAAACAAAAACCAAAGAGGUUUCAAAGGCUUUUGAAGAGGCCGAGCACAGUAGCUCAUGCCUGUAAUCCCAGCACUUUGGGAGGCCGAGGAGGACGGAUCACCUGAGGUCAGGAGUUCAAGACCAGCCUGGCCAACAUGGUGAAACCCCAUCUCUACUAAAAAUACAAAAAUUAGCCAGGUGUAGUGGUGCCCACCUGUAAUCCCAGCUACUCAGGAGGCUGAGACAGGAGAAUCGCUUGAACCGGGGAGGCGGAAGUUGCAGUGAGCUGAGAUUGCACCAUUGCAUUCCAGCCUGGGUGACAGGAGUGAAACUCCAUCUCAAAAAGAAAAAAAGCCUUUUGAAAACUAGAGGUGGGGGAUGGAGGCCUGGGCCGAGGCCACUGGUGCAUAUGUUCCCGGGAGGGAUAAGCCAGACCUGCCAACCUGGAAGAGGAAUUUCCGCUCUGCCCUCAACCGCAAAGAAGGGUUGCGUUUAGCAGAGGACCGGAGCAAGGACCCUCACGACCCACAUAAAAUCUACGAGUUUGUGAACUCAGGAGUUGGGGACUUUUCCCAGCCAGACACCUCUCCGGACACCAAUGGUGGAGGCAGUACUUCUGAUACCCAGGAAGACAUUCUGGAUGAGUUACUGGGUAACAUGGUGUUGGCCCCACUCCCAGAUCCGGGACCCCCAAGCCUGGCUGUAGCCCCUGAGCCCUGCCCUCAGCCCCUGCGGAGCCCCAGCUUGGACAAUCCCACUCCCUUCCCAAACCUGGGGCCCUCUGAGAACCCACUGAAGCGGCUGUUGGUGCCGGGGGAAGAGUGGGAGUUCGAGGUGACAGCCUUCUACCGGGGCCGCCAAGUCUUCCAGCAGACCAUCUCCUGCCCGGAGGGCCUGCGGCUGGUGGGGUCCGAAGUGGGAGACAGGACGCUGCCUGGAUGGCCAGUCACACUGCCAGACCCUGGCAUGUCCCUGACAGACAGGGGAGUGAUGAGCUACGUGAGGCAUGUGCUGAGCUGCCUGGGUGGGGGACUGGCUCUCUGGCGGGCCGGGCAGUGGCUCUGGGCCCAGCGGCUGGGGCACUGCCACACAUACUGGGCAGUGAGCGAGGAGCUGCUCCCCAACAGCGGGCAUGGGCCUGAUGGCGAGGUCCCCAAGGACAAGGAAGGAGGCGUGUUUGACCUGGGGCCCUUCAUUGUAGGCUCCUGGGCCCCCAGAUCUGAUUACCUUCACGGAAGGAAGCGGACGCUCACCACGCUAUGCCCUCUGGUUCUGUGUGGGGGAGUCAUGGCCCCAGGACCAGCCGUGGACCAAGAGGCUCGUGAUGGUCAAGGUUGUGCCCACGUGCCUCAGGGCCUUGGUAGAAAUGGCCCGGGUAGGGGGUGCCUCCUCCCUGGAGAAUACUGUGGACCUGCACAUUUCCAACAGCCACCCACUCUCCCUCACCUCCGACCAGUACAAGGCCUACCUGCAGGACUUGGUGGAGGGCAUGGAUUUCCAGGGCCCUGGGGAGAGCUGAGCCCUCGCUCCUCAUGGUGUGCCUCCAACCCCCCUGUUCCCCACCACCUCAACCAAUAAACUGGUUCCUGCUAUGA